UCGGCCUCCCAAAGUGCUGGGAUUACAGGCAUGAGCCACUGACGCCUGGCCAGCCUAUGCAUUUUUAAGAAAUUAUUCUGUAUUAGGUGCUGUGCUAAACAUUGGGCACUACAGUGACCAAAACAGACUGAAUUCCCCAAGAGCCAAAGACCAGUGAGGGAGACCAACAAGAAACAGGAAAUGCAAAAGAGACCAUUAUUACUCACUAUGACUAAGGGCCACAAAUGGGGUACGUUGAUGGAGAGUGAUUUGUUAAGAGACUACAGAGGGAGGACAGACUACCAAGAGGGGGGCCAGGAAAGCUCCUCUGACGAGGUGGUAUUUCAGCCCAAACUGGAAGAAUGAGAAAGAGCUAGCCAGCCAUCAGAAUAGUCCAGAAGAGAUGGGGAGCACUACACUCACUACACUUUGGCCUGAGAAAAUAGCAUGGGAUUGGAGGAGGCUGGGGGAACACCACUUCUGCCGACCUGGGCAGGAGGCAUUGAGGGCUUGAGAAAGGGCAAUGGCAGUAGCAGUAGAAAGGACAGGGUAGGAGCAGGGACUUUGCAGGUGGAAUCAUUAGGUCUUAUCAACAGAUAUGGGCAAGCAAAGCCAGGGGAGAAUUGAUGGUAAUGCUGAGGUUUGGAGCCAGGCUAGAUGGGACAGUGGUGGGUGAUGCAAAGGAAAGAGGUCAGGAAGCAGGGCCAGACGUGGGGAGAAGGUGUGGGGGUUUGGUUUCCAUCUUGCCGAGUCUGCCGGAAUGUGGAUGGGAAGACCAAGAGGAGGAGCAAGGGGCAGAGGGGAAGGGAAUCUUAAAGAAGUCCUGGAUGCCACACUCUUCUUCCUUCCUCCUCUUCCCUCUCCUCAGAGGUCUCACUCGUGGUUCUUCAUUUCCUGCCCUGCCUCCAUCUCCUCUGGGUGCUGGGAAAGUGGAGGAUUAGCUGAAGUUUUGCUUCUCGGGGCCUGUCUGAAUCUCCAUUGCUUUCUGGGAGGACAUAAUUCACCUGUCCUAGCUUCUUAUCAUCUUACAUUUCCCUGUAGCCACUGGGACAUAUGUGGUGUUCCUUCCUAGCUCCUGUCUCCUCCUCAUGCCUUUGCUGGGUAUGGGCAUGUUAGGGGGAAGGUCAUUGCUGUCAGAGGGGCACUGACUUUCUAAUGGUGUUACCCAAGGUGAAUGUUGGAGACACAGUCGCGAUGCUGCCCAAGUCCCGGCGAGCCCUAACUAUCCAGGAGAUCGCUGCGCUGGCCAGGUCCUCCCUGCAUGGUAUUUCCCAGGUGGUGAAGGACCACGUGACCAAGCCUACCGCCAUGGCCCAGGGCCGAGUGGCUCACCUCAUUGAGUGGAAGGGCUGGAGCAAGCCGAGUGACUCACCUGCUGCCCUGGAAUCAGCCUUUUCCUCCUAUUCAGACCUCAGCGAGGGCGAACAAGAGGCUCGCUUUGCAGCAGGAGUGGCUGAGCAGUUUGCCAUCGCGGAAGCCAAGCUCCGAGCAUGGUCUUCGGUGGAUGGCGAGGACUCCACUGAUGACUCCUAUGAUGAGGACUUUGCUGGGGGAAUGGACACAGACAUGGCUGGGCAGCUGCCCCUGGGGCCGCACCUCCAGGACCUGUUCACCGGCCACCGGUUCUCCCGGCCUGUGCGCCAGGGCUCCGUGGAGCCUGAGAGCGACUGCUCACAGACCGUGUCCCCAGACACCCUGUGCUCUAGUCUGUGCAGCCUGGAGGAUGGGUUGUUGGGCUCCCCGGCCCGGCUGGCCUCCCAGCUGCUGGGCGAUGAGCUGCUUCUCGCCAAACUGCCCCCCAGCCGGGAAAGUGCCUUCCGCAGCCUGGGCCCACUGGAGGCCCAGGACUCACUCUACAACUCGCCCCUCACAGAGUCCUGCCUUUCCCCCGCGGAGGAGGAGCCAGCCCCCUGCAAGGACUGCCAGCCACUCUGCCCACCACUAACGGGCAGCUGGGAACGGCAGCGGCAAGCCUCUGACCUGGCCUCUUCUGGGGUGGUGUCCUUAGAUGAGGAUGAGGCAGAGCCAGAGGAACAGUGACCCACAUCAUGCCUGGCAGUGGCAUGCAUCCCCCGGCUGCUGCCAGGGGCAGAGCCUCUGUGCCCAAGUGUGGGCUCAAGGCUCCCAGCAGAGCUCCACAGCCUAGAGGGCUCCUGGGAGCGCUCGCUUCUCCGUUGUGUGUUUUGCAUGAAAGUGUUUGGAGAGGAGGCAGGGGCUGGGCUGGGGGCGCAUGUCCUGCCCCCACUCCCGGGGCUUGCCGGGGGUUGCCCGGGGCCUCUGGGGCAUGGCUACAGCUGUGGCAGACAGUGAUGUUCAUGUUCUUAAAAUGCCACACACACAUUUCCUCCUCGGAUAAUGUGAACCACUAAGGGGGUUGUGACUGGGCUGUGUGAGGGUGGGGUGGGAGGGGGCCCAGCAACCCCCCACCCUCCCCAUGCCUCUCUCUUCUCUGCUUUUCUUCUCACUUCCGAGUCCAUGUGCAGUGCUUGAUAGAAUCACCCCCACCUGGAGGGGCUGGCUCCUGCCCUCCCGGAGCCUAUGGGUUGAGCCGUCCCUCAAGGGCCCCUGCCCAGCUGGGCUCGUGCUGUGCUUCAUUCACCUCUCCAUCGUCUCUAAAUCUUCCUCUUUUUUCCUAAAGACAGAAGGUUUUUGGUCUGUUUUUUCAGUCGGAUCUUCUCUUCUCUGGGAGGCUUUGGAAUGAUGAAAGCAUGUACCCUCCACCCUUUUCCUGGCCCCCUAAUGGGGCCUGGGCCCUUUCCCAACCCCUCCUAGGAUGUGCGGGCAGUGUGCUGGCGCCUCACAGCCAGCCGGGCUGCCCAUUCACGCAGAGCUCUCUGAGCGGGAGGUGGAAGAAAGGAUGGCUCUGGUUGCCACAGAGCUGGGACUUCAUGUUCUUCUAGAGAGGGCCACAAGAGGGCCACAGGGGUGGCCGGGAGUUGUCAGCUGAUGCCUGCUGAGAGGCAGGAAUUGUGCCAGUGAGUGACAGUCAUGAGGGAGUGUCUCUUCUUGGGGAGGAAAGAAGGUAGAGCCUUUCUGUCUGAAUGAAAGGCCAAGGCUACAGUACAGGGCCCCACCCCAGCCAGGGUGUUAAUGCCCACGUAGUGGAGGCCUCUGGCAGAUCCUGCAUUCCAAGGUCACUGGACUGUACGUUUUUAUGGUUGUGGGAAGGGUGGGUGGCUUUAGAAUUAAGGGCCUUGUAGGCUUUGGCAGGUAAGAGGGCCCAAGGUAAGAACGAGAGCCAACGGGCACAAGCAUUCUAUAUAUAAGUGGCUCAUUAGGUGUUUAUUUUGUUCUAUUUAAGAAUUUGUUUUAUUAAAUUAAUAUAAAAAUCUUUGUAAAUCUCUA